GGGCUUCCUGUGCUUCUCCCUGGCGUUCUGCGCACAGGUGCAGGUGGUGUUCUGGAGACUCCACAGCCCCACCCAGCACCCAUCCUUCCGUCCUGGAUGCUGACCUGCCUGGAGGAGGGUCCGGCCUAGCUGACCGUGGGCAGGGGCCAAGGGCGUCCCCGUGGAAAGGCCAGCAGCUUGGAGAGGAAGGAGGCCUCCCUGGCCCAGCAGAGAAUGAGAGCUCGGUAGCAGAGCCAGCCCCACCUUCCCCUUGAGAGCCAGACCUGGUGAGAGCCCCCAGGGCAGCCGGGCGGCACCAGGGACAGCCACGGGCAGGGUCAUGGAGUGGGGCAGGAGAGCCUGGCAGGUCACAAGAGGUGAUUUCUUGGAGCCCUAGCUGGAGUCCUAGUGGCCUCGUGUAUUCAAGUGCCUGGUUGCCCAGGGCCCUCAAACACAGGCUUGGCCAUGAGAGAUACCGAGGCUGGUAGCAGGCAGGUCCUCUGGCUGAGCUCUGCAGGGGGCCUGCUGUGCAGUUUCUUGAGCUGUGCUGGCAGCCUGAGUGUGGUGGUCCCCACCGUGGUUUGCAAAUGGGGGGACUCAGGCCCUCUGGGGGUGGGGGGAGCUCAAGGUUACCCUGGCAGUGCCGGGGCUGGAUGGGGGCUCCAGGCUUACGACAAAGGCUCUUGGCCCCAAAGUGCCCACCCACCCCUGGCAUCAUUUGGGAGGAACCGCCUGAACCAGGUGGGAGAAACACCAUUUUAUCAGGCCCAGAAGGAUCCCAGAGGGGCUGAGCCCCCAGAAGAGGGCUGUGGCUUUGAGGACUGGCACAGGAGUCUUACCAGGGUGGUGAGCUGGGCCAGGGCCCACCAGAGCCGAAUGGGCUUCAACCUUGGGCUCCCUGUCCAACAAAGUCCUGCUGGCAGCCUAGACAGUGGCAAAGGCCAAAGGCCCCAAGCUGUUGGCACCGGAAACGUCGAGGUGGAGGACGCCAUGCUGGACACCUACGACCUGGUAUAUGAGCAGGCGAUGAAAGUUUCUGUGCUGUGGGAAGAAGUCUCCUUUCAGCCGUCUGGGGAGCACAGAGGCUGACCUGUGUCAGGGAGAGGAGGCGGCGAGAGAGGUGAGGGGGGGACCUGGAUGCUGGCCAGGCAAGACCCUCGGGGGCUGGACACCCUGGGGCCCAACCCCAAGACCCAGGGCCAUCCUCCCACCCCACCCCUUGGCCUCCCCAGACCCUUGGGAACUGCCGCUGAAGGGCUCAGGGAAGGUUCUGAUGUGAUCGGAGGCUAGUUAGGGUUCAUGGUACGCCAAGCCCAUUGGGUGGCCAGGCUGGGCUCAAGACAUAAACACAGGCCCCUUUGCCCAGCUGGACGCAGGCCCCAUGCGCCAUUCACUCCUUCAAGCCAGUUCCAGCCUGGGGACUUCCCAAGGCCAGCUAAGUCCACAGAAGCCUCUUGGAGUGCACCCAUGAGGGCUCUGUGCCAAGGGCUGCAGGGCUGGUGUGGUGGGCUCUGUCUAGGGGGAAGGGUGCAGGCGUCCUGGGGGGCAUCAGAAGGAGUUGAAGGGCACUCAGAGGAGAAGAAGUAGGCCAGGGUGUGGCCAGGGCUUCAGCAACAACAGAGCGGGGCCCGAGGCCAGGAAGCCUUUCCUCCCCAGGGCCCUGGGAGAGACUGGGCCCUCCUCUCUUUCUCCUGGUGCCCGGCAGCCCUCCCCCAGCCCACCCUGCCCCCUCCCUGCUCCCCUCCCCGCUCCCCUCCCCUACUGUCCUGGAAACAAACCCACCCUAUCUCACAGUGGGAGGCACCUGGCGACCCUCCAAGAAACAGAGGGGAGGAGAGCAAAUGGCUGGAGGCCUGGUGAGGGGUGGAGCCACAGCCAAGGCUCUGAGGGCAGAAGGGCUGGCGCUGAGGAUGGUGCUGGGGAGGGACCAGCGGCAUUGGGGGCAGGGCUAACAGUCAGGACCCCUGUGCCACCCAAGGAGAGACUGAAAAGGCCCCCGACUGAAAAGCAGGAGCGAGGGCCUGCCUCGAGCACCCUUGGGAUGGCAGGGCCAUGGGCCCGACUGCAAAGCCUCCUGGGGAGCCGGAAGAGCCAGCACAGGCGGCAGGCACGGAGCCACCCAGAUGGGCUGGCAUGGGCGGGAGGGAGGCAGACCUGCCUGCGGGGGACAGGAGGGUGAGCCCUGAGACCCUGCGGAGGCCUCCACAGGCCGCCCCAGUUGCCAUCAUCUCCAGGGUUCAGAGACAGGCCUGCCACCUCCCUUUUCUGAAAAGAUGCCUCUGGGUGCCAUGCCCUGGGGUGGCACUGGAAGCCUGGGAUGGAACCAGGAAGCUGGGACUGUGCGGGGACCCCCCUCACACCCCUCCACCAGCUGGCUUCCUGCCCUCCCUGUUAGCCAUCACCCUCUGGUCACCAAGGUGCUGUGCCCGGCCCUGGGCUGGAUGCUGGGAACCCAGAGUGAAUUCGAAGUGGCCCGGCCCAGGGGAGCCAACGUGUGGCCCAACAUGGACGCUCAGGACAGCUGGGAGACGGCACCGGCCGGGCCCAGGGCAGUGCCAGAGUGCCCACAGAGGCCAGCCCUGUCCCACUGGGCUUCACCUGCUCGUGCUGCCUUUCCCUAGAGCCCUGGGGGCUUCCUAGGAAUGUGCCGCACCCGCCGCCCUGCUGCCCUGGCAUUGGCCUAGGUGGGCGCUGCAGCUCCAUGGCCCCACAGAGGCCGCUUGUCCAGGCAGGGAGGGCCGCUCAGGGCGGGUACCAUGCCUGCUGCCCUCUCACAGGACUGCCUUCAGGGCAUCCGGAGCUUCCUGAGGACACACCAGCAGGUCGCCUCCAGCCUGACCAGCAUCGGCCUGGCCCUCACGGUACCCUCUCGCCUCCCUCACUGCCCCUUCCCACCUCCUGCCCCUCAGCCUGCCCAGCCCCCGACUCAGAUGGAAGGGUGACCCGGGACAGGAUCUCUGGUCUUGAGCCUCACUGGCUGCCAACCUCAGGGAGCUGCUCUGGUGUGACAGGGCCUGCCUCCUACAGCUGGGCCGCCCCCUUACACUGCAGAGUCCUGAUGCUUCCUGGGGAGGGGCGCCCGCACCCUGGGGCAGUGGGGCAGCCGCGGGUGUCUCCCUCCCAGGUGUCCGCCUUGCUCUUCAGCUCCUUCCUGUGGUUUGCCAUCCGCUGUGGCUGCAGCUUGGACCGCAAGGGCAAAUACACCCUGACCCCACGGUAGGGCCCCCUG